ACUCGCGCUGCGGCCAGCGCCCGGGCCUGCGGGCCCGGGCGGCGGCUGUGUUGCGCAGUCUUCAUGGGUUCCCGACGAGGAGGUCUCUGUGGCUGCGGCGGCGGCUGCUAACUGCGCCACCUGCUGCAGCCUGUCCCCGCCGCUCUGAAGCGGCCGCGUCGAAGCCGAAAUGCCGCCACCCCGGACCGGCCGAGGCCUUCUCUGGCUGGGUCUGGUUCUGAGCUCCGUCUGCGUCGCCCUCGGAUCCGAAACGCAGGCCAACUCGACCACAGAUGCUCUGAACGUUCUUCUCAUCAUCGUGGAUGACCUGCGCCCCUCCCUGGGCUGUUAUGGGGAUAAGCUGGUGAGGUCCCCAAAUAUUGACCAACUGGCAUCCCACAGCCUCCUCUUCCAGAAUGCCUUUGCGCAGCAAGCAGUGUGCGCCCCGAGCCGCGUUUCUUUCCUCACUGGCAGGAGACCUGACACCACCCGCCUGUACGACUUCAACUCCUACUGGAGGGUGCACGCUGGAAACUUCUCCACCAUCCCCCAGUACUUCAAGGAGAAUGGCUAUGUGACCAUGUCGGUGGGAAAAGUCUUUCACCCUGGGAUAUCUUCUAACCAUACCGAUGAUUCUCCGUAUAGCUGGUCUUUUCCACCUUAUCAUCCUUCCUCUGAGAAGUAUGAAAACACUAAGACAUGUCGAGGGCCAGAUGGAGAACUCCAUGCCAACCUGCUUUGCCCUGUGGAUGUGCUGGAUGUUCCCGAGGGCACCUUGCCUGACAAACAGAGCACUGAGCAAGCCAUACAGUUGUUGGAAAAGAUGAAAACGUCAGCCAGUCCUUUCUUCCUGGCCGUUGGGUAUCAUAAGCCACACAUCCCCUUCAGAUACCCCAAGGAAUUUCAGAAGUUGUAUCCCUUGGAGAACAUCACCCUGGCCCCCGAUCCCGAGGUCCCUGAUGGCCUACCCCCUGUGGCCUACAACCCCUGGAUGGACAUCAGGCAACGGGAAGACGUCCAAGCCUUAAACAUCAGUGUGCCGUAUGGUCCAAUUCCUGUGGACUUUCAGCGGAAAAUCCGCCAGAGCUACUUUGCCUCUGUGUCAUAUUUGGAUACACAGGUCGGCCGCCUCUUGAGUGCUUUGGACGAUCUUCAGCUGGCCAACAGCACCAUCAUUGCAUUUACCUCGGAUCAUGGGUGGGCUCUAGGUGAACAUGGAGAAUGGGCCAAAUACAGCAAUUUUGAUGUUGCUACCCAUGUUCCCCUGAUAUUCUAUGUUCCUGGAAGGACGGCUUCACUUCCGGAGGCAGGCGAGAAGCUUUUCCCUUACCUCGACCCUUUUGAUUCCGCCUCACAGUUGAUGGAGCCAGGCAGGCAAUCCAUGGACCUUGUGGAACUUGUGUCUCUUUUUCCCACGCUGGCUGGACUUGCAGGACUGCAGGUUCCACCUCGCUGCCCCGUUCCUUCAUUUCACGUUGAGCUGUGCAGAGAAGGCAAGAACCUUCUGAAGCAUUUUCGAUUCCGUGACUUGGAAGAGGAUCCGUACCUCCCUGGUAAUCCCCGUGAACUGAUUGCCUAUAGCCAGUAUCCCCGGCCUUCAGACAUCCCUCAGUGGAAUUCUGACAAGCCGAGUUUAAAAGAUAUAAAGAUCAUGGGCUAUUCCAUACGCACCAUAGACUAUAGGUAUACUGUGUGGGUUGGCUUCAAUCCUGAUGAAUUUCUAGCUAACUUUUCUGACAUCCAUGCAGGGGAACUGUAUUUUGUGGAUUCUGACCCAUUGCAGGAUCACAAUAUGUAUAAUGAUUCCCAAGGUGGAGAUCUUUUCCAGUUGUUGAUGCCUUGAGUUUUGCCAACCAUGGAUGGCAAAUGUGAUGUGCUCCCUUCCAGCUGGUGAGAGGAGGAGUUAGAGCUGGUCGUUUUGUGAUUACCCAUAAUAUUGGAAGCAGCCUGAGGGCUAGUUAAUCCAAACAUGCAUCAACAAUUUGGCCUGAGAAUAUGUAACAGCCAAACCUUUUCGUUUAGUCUUUAUUAAAAUUUAUAAUUGGUAAUUGGACCAGUUUUUUUUUUAAUUUCCCUCUUUUUAAAACAGUUACGGCUUAUUUACUGAAUAAAUACAAAGCAAACAAACUCAAGUUAUGUCAUACCUUUGGAUACGAAGACCAUACAUAAUAACCAAACAUAACAUUAUACACAAAGAAUACUUUCAUUAUUUGUGGAAUUUAGUGCAUUUCAAAAAGUAAUCAUAUAUCAAACUAGGCACCACACUAAGUUCCUGAUUAUUUUGUUUAUAAUUUAAUAAUAUAUCUUAUGAGCCCUAUAUAUUCAAAAUAUUAUGUUAACAUGUAAUCCAUGUUUCUUUUUCAAAUCUAAAGUUAAAAAAAAAUAGCAGAAGCCAGUGUCUUAAAGUCUAUCUUUUGUUUCUAAGACCAUGGGAUUUCAUAAUCUCAAGAUAAAAUAUGUAUGAAGUAAUUAAUGUAGAAUUUUUACACCAAAUAAUAAAUAAUGCUUAAUAAACUAGAGAUAUGAGAUGUGUAGGAAAUUUGGUUAAACUUUUUUCAGAUACUUUCUGGCCCAAAUAAUAAUUUGUUAGCAAAUAAUAUGACCCUUGAACUCAAUGGCCAUCUAUUAAAAGACUGUUGUUCACACUGGAAAACAUUUAAAGAUGUGACUAUAUCCAUGGGUGGAUUGAAUCACUCAAAAUAUAUUAGUAUCCUUCUUUAGGGAUGGUUGGUUACAGACAUGUAUUUAUUCAGGAGGCAGAAAAUAUUCCAUUUUAAUUGCUUAUUAAAGAAAACAUUAAAUUCUAAAUUAUUUUGAGGACUGUGAAGACUUUUCAUUAGUGUAAUAUUAGGUCAUUGUCAAUCUCCCAGAAUGUAGUUCUAUAUUCUCUAAAUAUGAAAGUAUCCAGAAAGGCCAGUGGUAGUAAAAAGCUUAGUGUAUAUAAUCUCAAAAGGGAUGGAAUAUUUACAACUCAUAUUUAUAACAUGUUGAAUCUUCUCAGUUAUCAGUAGUCAUCAGAAGUGUCAAUAGCUUUCUAAAUAAAUAUUAAAUAUCUACUGUCCUGUAGUGAAGGAGUAAUUUUUAGUAAUUUUCUCUUUACAAAGUCUCCAGUGUUUCCAGGUAAAUAUUUGUGAAACAAAAUACAGCAAACUACAUUGUUACUUCAGUGUAUUGUUGCCAAAAAUGACAAGAUAUUAUAUUAAAAUCAGUAAAUUUUAGACAGAUUUUAAAAAUUAAUUAGCCUACAAUAGAGGUUAUAUGGUAACACGGUGAUCUUCUAAGCAGUUAAGUGACUGACUGUUCUGGCAACAACGACUUCUCCGUGACUGAAGGGCCCUGUUCAUUUCCUGAUCCUGAAGCUCGUCUCUCUUUUGAGCCUCCGCUUGCUUUGGUCGAUGGUUUCCCUCAGCUUUUUCUUUGCUGUUCUUCAUCCUCGUUGUUGCUGUCAUCAUGUUCACUGUGGCUUUUACAAUACAGCCUGUAAAUUCCUUAUGACAUAGUUCAGUGCAUUUGGCUUUAUUGCCUGCUCCACAGUUCUUUACCUUUACUUGGCUUAGAGAAACUGUAUCUUUGUUGCUUCAUAUAACCUUUCCCCAACCCCACUAAGCUGGACAUAACUUAUUAGUGGUCCUCCCGUCACUUUAUUUGUAGAAAUCUCUCUUUCACAUGAGCAGGGGUUCUUUCAUGUGGUUUAGCUGACAGCAGAACUAGUGAUUCUAGACAUUUUGCAUGGCCCUCAUUCAGUGGCUCACAAACAUGAGGGAGCAUCAGAACUACUUGAGGGGCUUGUUAAAACCCAGUGCGUUAGAAGUCGGAUGCGGUGGCUCACACCUGUAAUCCCAGCACUUUGGGAGGCCCAGGCAGGCGGAUCACUUGAGGUUAGGAGUUCAAGACCAGCCUGGCCAACAUGGUGAAACCCCGUCUCUACUAAAAAUACAAAAGUUAGCCGGGUGUGGUGGUGCAUGCCUGUAAUCCCAGCUUCUUGGGAGGCCAAGGCACAAGAAUCGCUUGAACCAGGAGACGGAGGUUUCAGUGAAUGAAGAUCGUGCCAUUGUAUUCCAGCCUCGGCAACACAGCAGGACUGUGAUUUUCUUUGGAGACUCCUAGAUUUUCUGUGGUUUUGAACUGAAUUUGUUGGAUGUUGGCAAGUGCCUCUUAUGAGCUGUUUCUUUAUCCUGCAUUUGCCCCACAAAGACUUAUCUGGAGGUGAGCAAAGUAUGUUUGGUAGUGAGGUCACAAAGGCAAUCAGCCCCUUCCUCCCCACUCCCAUUGCCAUCUUCUCAGUCCUUCUCCCUUUCUUUCCAAGUAGUUUACCCACCCCUCCUCUUUCCUCCCCUGUCCCUAAAAUAAUCCACGUGUCUUCCUAAAAUCUCUCUUUGAUCCUGUCCUUUGAUAACACCGUCAGUGCCUACUACUGGGUCUAGACAGACCUCUGUUGAGCAGUCAGAGUCUUCCCUGACUCCACAAUGCCCCUUUCCUUGGCUGACCAGUAUGACUACUGGUCCCCACCUUUCCCUUGCCUAUCCCUACCUCCCUCCUACUAGGUUGUCCCAUCCCUCUCUUCACCCAUUCAUUCAUGACCAUUUUUCACUACCAAGCUCCCCCCCUCCCGAAGGAGGCUGAGGUUUUUGUGACUCUCUAGACUCUAUUGUGGGAUGGAAUGAACAUUGCUAAAGAAUCUUGUGUUCGCUUUACUUUAAAAAGGUAUUUUUUUCCUAAUUAUAAAACUGAUGUGUCAGUUACGGAAAAAUUAGAAAUGCAGCACAAAUACAUGAAUAUUUUACCACAAAAUUGCCAUAUAAUAUCUUGUCUUUUUUGGGGGUGUGAAUUUUUUGCAUUGUUCUGGUCAUAUUCUUUAUCAUGUAAUUUAUGUUCUUUUUUACUAAGUAUUAUGUGUGGUUAUUAUAGAUUUUCACAAAGAUAUAUUGCUGGUAAUAUAUUUUAUUGUGUAGUCUUAUAAUUUACUUAACCUUCUUUCAAUUGUUAGAAAUUUAGGCUAUUUCCAGAUUUUCAGUAUUGUAAAUAAUGCUGUGAUGACCAAUUUUGUGAAUAAAAUGUUUUUAUGUAUUUCAGAUUAUUCCCUUAGGAUAGUCUCUCAGUGCCAAGUUGUCAAAAACAUCUCUAUUUUGCUUAUCUUCCUGCUCUCUUGCUGCCUUAGGGGGUAGUAAACUGAAACAUAAAGUAAACAUGCAUACAAAUAAAAAACAUAAAACAAAAAUAAGCAACCUGAUGGUAAUAGGUGAAAGUGGUAACCUGUUUUAACUUUGAAUUCUUGCCGGGCGCGGUGGCUCACGCCUGUAAUCCCAGCACUUUGGGAGGCUGAGGCGGGUGGAUCACGAGGUCAGGAGUUCAAAACCAGCCUGGCCAAGAUGGUGAAAUCCCGUCUCUACUAAAAAUACAAAAAUUAGCCGGGCGUGGUGGCGGGCGCCUGUAAUCCCAGCUACUUGGGAGGCUGAGGCAGAGAAUUGCUUGAACCCAGGAGGCGGAGGUUGCAGUGAGCCAAGAUCGCGCCACUGCACUCCAGCCUGGGUGACAGAGCGAGACUCCGUCUCAAAUAAAAAACAACAAAAAACAAAAAAAACUUAAAAUUCUUUGCUUGUUAGUGACCUUGAUCAUGGUUCUCUUUGUACGAUAGUUGGGCAUCUGUAUUUCCACUUGUGUGAAUUUGCCUUUAAAUUUUGGUUAUGGGUUUCACCUUUUAAAAUAAUCAAACAUAUUUAUCUUUUCCUGUGUGAUAGGUUUUUUUCUGUAUCUUUUCCUGUUAAACACACAGACCCCUCCCCAAUCUGGACAUUGAAUAAAUAUUCAUUUUCCUUUGCAUUGUUUGGGGUUUGGUUUUAUGCUUACUGUGUCUCUCCACCCCAUUAUCAGAGUAAUAUAUGCUCAUUGCAUAAAAUCUGGAACAUGUGAAAACUGGAGAUGAAAAGAAGCCCAGCAUUUGAGACAUACCCACUGCUGACAUUUGUAUAUUUCCUUUCAUUCUUUUACCUGCCUAAAGACAUAUAUGCAGAUAUGGACAUAUUUAGCUUUACAUACAUGCAGACUACCACAUAUAAUCUAUAUCUUGUUUUUUUGAUCUAACACAAUGUUAGCUUGGUUUUUUAUGUCAUUGACAGUUCUUGAUUAACAGCUGUAAUGGCUGCACAGCCCUGCUUCAUUAAUUUUUUUUUUUGGACUGAAAUGUAUGUACCACGUUCCGCUUAUCCAUUCAUCCACCAGUGACCACUUGGGUCAUUUCUACCUUUUGGCCAUUGCAAUAAUGUUGCUGUCAACAAGGAUGUACAAAUAUCUGUUCGAGUCCCUGCUCUUAAUUGUUUUGGGUAUACACCCAACCUACAUUAAUCUUUAAUCACUUAAGAUGUUGGGGUUUGUGCUGGGAGGUAACCAAGUGACUCUGGAGCAGCCUCACCCUAGCUACAGAGGGAAACUGACUCUUCCCUCUCUGCCCAAUCUUUUGCCGCCUGUCAGGUUCCCAAGCUGUCCAUACCUUACUGUGUGAAGCGCUUUGGGUAUAAACUCCCAAAUAGAGGCUCAGCCCCUUUUCCUUUCCCAAGUCCAUCCUGCAGGUUAUAGCUCUUCAGAGGAAUCUCUUGAAUUCUGGCCUGGGAUCUGGGAUUAAAGUAGAACCCAGGGUGUCCCUUGGGGCCUUAGGCAUAGCCCGUUGUGGUGGAACCUGCCAUCAGCCCCACUGCACUCAGUGGUCCCCUGGUACUUCAGGACAGUUUCUCUCUUCUGCACAUGAGAACUUCAAGCAGAGAGGACUGUCAGUUGUUGCCUUCACAUCACCAAUCGUUUGGCCAUAAUGGCCAAGAGCCCUCACUGCUCUUGGGUCUUGCCUUUCCACAUGUUACUGAAAGCUCCCGUUGGUGUCCCUGUCCACUAACUCACCUGAUGGGACAGAUGCCACUUUCCUCUGAGUGUCUGAUAAAACACAGUCUGUUGUGGGGAGCCCACGCUCAAGGGUUUUCUUUGGGAUCAGAGUUUCCCGGCUAUUACUCCAUGCCCUGCCUGACAUCACUGUCAUGUAUGGUGCUAAUCACCAAAGGAUGCCCUUGUUUGAUUCUGGAUUCUAGGUGAUAGUCCUUAUCCUCUGAUGGGGGAAGAGUUUGGGUGGGAGAGAACAAACCGACAAGUUGGUUCCAGAUGAGGUGGCUGGGAGCCAACCCUCAGGUACUUGGCUCUGAGUAAUGUGACGGCCCAGGCAAGAGGGCUCCCACUGCCAAUGAGGAACAAAAGCUCAAGGUCUAGUAGUGUAUUCAGCACAUGCUAGGAAACAAGAGUUGGGACGUGGACAAGGAGAGGAGCAAAGGCCAGGGGUUAACUGCUUUUGGUUUUUCCUCUAUAAAAGUCAGGGACUAUGAUUUAUAUGGGUGAGAAGGUUUGGAGUAGGACUGAAGCUGCCAUUUACAAACCCCUUGCCCUAAUUUAUUGUAGUUUUGGGUGUGUUUCUGAAAGAACCUUUUGCAGGUGAUUUUUAUUCAGUACUCAUUAACUUACAGCUUUUAUGAAUUCACAUCUUCUACACUAUUGAAAAACAUAAGUUUGUAUUGUGUUAAGUGCAGCAUGAGUUAUUAUAUGAAUAAAUCACAUUAAAUUUGCCA